AGUUCCUUCCGGUGCGCCUCCCGCUCGCCCUUGCGGAGGCCCUGAGGGCGGAUUCAAGGCCCCGCGAGAAGCCAUCUGAGGCGGCGACGACUGUUCUCAGCCCCACGGGAACGCCGCGGACGCAGCGUCCCUCUCCCGGACAAGAAAACAGCCAUUCUAGAAAGCUUCAAAAAGGACACACUAGAUUUAAUUAGAAAUGUUAAGAUUGCCCAAAAAAGGAUUACCUAGAUUUGAGCAAGUUCAGGAUGAAGACACCUACCUGGAAAAUUUAGCAAUACAAAGAAAUGCAUCUGCUUUUUUUGAAAAAUAUGAUCGGAGUGAAAUACAAGAGUUACUAACUACUGCACUAGUUAGCUGGUUGUCUGCCAAAGAGGAUGUGCGCUCUCAAGUAGACCUCCCAUGUGGAAUUAUGAGUCAAAUGAAUAACGUAGGCUUCUCCACUGCAAUCCUACUGACUCCCGUGGACCCUACUGCCCUCUUAGACUAUAGAGAGGUCCAUCAAAUGAUAAGAGAGUUGGCUAUUGGAAUUUAUUGCCUAAAUCAAAUCCCUUCCAUCAGUUUAGAAGCUAAUUAUGAUCAGAGUUCUUCUUGUCAAUUACCUCCAGCUUAUUAUGAUACCAGAAUUGGGCAAAUUCUGAUCAAUAUUGACUACAUGCUGAAAGCACUAUGGCAUGGAAUAUAUAUGCCCAAAGAAAAACGAGCUAGAUUCUCUGAAUUGUGGCGUGCCAUCAUGGACAUUGAUCCUGAUGGAAAACCUCAAACAAAUAAAGACAUUUUUUCAGAGUUUAGUUCAGCAGGUUUGACUGAUAUUACAAAGGAUCCAGACUUUAAUGAAAUCUAUGAUGAAGACGUGAAUGAAGAUCCAACAUAUGAUCCCAACAGCCCUGAAGAAACAGCUGUAUUUAUGAAAUAUGCUGAAAAUAUUAUGCUAAAGUUAACAUUCAGUACCACACAAAUUCAACAGUAUGAAAAUGUCUUUAUAUUUGAAACAGGCUAUUGGCUUACUAAUGCUAUAAAAUAUAAUCAGGAUUAUCUUGAUAUCUGUACCUACCAGAGACUACAGCAAAGAUUAUAUCUUCAAAAAAAGAUUAUUCAAAAACACUUUGAGAAGAAAAAAGAUAUCAGAAGAGGGAUAGGAUACCUAAAGUUAAUAUGUUUUCUGAUUCCAUUUCUACUGAGUUUAAAGAAGAAAAUGAAAGUUCCAUAUUUAAGUAGUCUGCUUCAGCCUUUUUCAGAUGACAAGGUCAAGACAGAGCGAGAAUUGCCUCCAUUUAUUUAUGGAAGAGAUUUUAAAUGCCAGAAUUUUCACUACAAAGAGAAUCAAUAUUUUCAUGUUCAUGGAGGAAUUGAAUUUGAUAUCAGCACCCCUUCAAUUGAGAAUGCCUUGGAAGAUUUUCAGAAAAAUUUAGAAAAAAUACGAGAUUGUGCUGCUAAUACAUUUAUAGAAGAUUCAGGAUAUAAAGAAUAUUACUCAAUACCAGUCAUGGAAUUUCAUGGAAAAAGCUACUAUGUGAUCUAUUUUGAACUAGAAACUUUCUAUCAGCAACUAUAUAAGACACAGUGGUGGGGAGCCAUAAAUGAAAUAGUGAACAAUCUGAGACUGAAAAGACUUCCACUGACAGAUGCUCAAUUACAUGAACAAUUUAAGAAAAAGCUUGGUUUCAAAAGAGCUAUGAAAUGCAAGAGUAUUCCAUUUGGUAUGAAGUCCGCUGUUGAAAGAGGGUUGUCUGCAGUUUUCCACACAUUUAGCCGUAAAACCUCAAGCUCAACAAUCAAUGUUUCAGAUGAAGCAGGUUAUACUAUUUUUCAUCAUGCUGCCCUGCACAACAGAGUUUCUAUUAUAUGUCAACUGUGCAAUGCUAACUUCAAGGUCAACCAGAGGCGCUUUGUUACGUUCAGCCAAGGUCCAACACCUCUACACCUUGCUGCACAGGCUUGCUCAUUAGAAACAACAGUUUGUCUACUGUGUUCCAAAGCUGAUUACACGCUUUCUGAAAAAAGAGGCUGGAUGCCGAUUCACUUUGCCGCUUUCUAUGACAACGUUUGCAUCAUUAUUGCUCUCUGUAGGAAGGAUCCUAGUUUGCUAGAAGCUGAGGCAACAGCUGAGAAUCAGUGCACUCCACUGUUACUUGCUGCCACUUCAGGAGCACUGGACACUAUUCAAUACCUGUUUUCUAUCGGUGCUAACUGGAGAAAAACAGAUAUUAAAGGAAAUAAUAUAAUCCAUUUAUCAGUGUUAACCUUUCAUACAGAGGUUCUCAAAUAUAUAAUAAAAUUAAAUAUUCCUGAACUCCCAGUGUGGAAAACUUUGGUAGAAAUGUUACAGUGUGAAAGCUAUAAACGAAGGAUGAUGGCCGUCAUGUCCUUGGAAGUAAUUUGCUUAGCAAAUGAUCAAUACUGGAGAUGUAUUUUGGAUGCAGGCACCAUUCCUGCCUUAAUCAAUCUAUUAAAAAGUUCCAAAAUAAAACUGCAGUGCAAAACUGUUGGGUUAUUGAGUAAUAUCUCAACCCACAAAAGUGCAGUGCAUGCUUUGGUAGAAGCGGGAGGCAUUCCAUCUCUAAUCAACCUACUGGUUUGUGAUGAGCCUGAAGUACACUCUCGCUGUGCUGUCAUUCUAUAUGAUAUUGCUCAAUGUGAAAACAAGGAUGUUAUUGCCAAAUAUAAUGGAAUCCCAAGCCUGAUAAAUCUAUUGAACUUAAACAUAGAAAAUGUGCUAGUAAAUGUAAUGAACUGUAUACGGGUAUUGUGUAUAGGAAAUGAAAACAAUCAAAGAGCUGUGAGAGAACAUAAAGGCCUCCCAUAUCUUAUCAGAUUUCUGAGUUCUGAUUCAGGUUUAUUUAACUUGUUCUUAAAUUCAUUUGAAGAUGUGUUGAAGGCUGUAUCUUCUGCUGCAAUUGCUGAGGUUGGGCGUGACAAUAAGGAAAUUCAGGAUGCUAUAGCUAUGGAGGGAGCGAUUCCUCCUCUGGUGGCUCUUUUUAAAGGGAAACAAAUUAGUGUCCAAAUGAAAGGUGCAAUGGCUGUGGAAUCACUGGCAAGUCACAACGCUCUUAUACAGAAAGCAUUUCUGGAAAAAUCGUUAACUAAAUAUCUUUUAAAACUCCUAAAGGCAUUUCAAAUAGAUGUUAAGGAACAAGGAGCUGUUGCACUUUGGGCCUUGGCAGGACAAACACUAAAACAACAAAAAUAUAUGGCAGAACAAAUUGGAUACAGCUUUAUAAUAAAUAUGCUUUUGUCACCAUCAGCUAAAAUGCAGUAUGUUGGAGGUGAAGCUGUCAUAGCUCUAAGUAAGGACAGCAGGAUGCAUCAAAAUCAAAUAUGUGAAGGGAAUGGAAUUGCACCAUUGGUUCGCUUACUAAGAAUUAGUACGAUUGCUGAAGGCACACUUCUCAGUGUCAUCAGAGCAGUGGGAUCCAUUUGUAUUGGUGUAGCCCAUACAAGCAAUCCUGUCAGUCAACAAUUGGUUGUAGAUGAAAAUGCCUUUCCAGUACUUAUCCAACUACUAAGAAAUCACCCUUCUCCUAACAUUAAGGUUGAAGUGGCAUUUUCCUUGGCAUGCAUUGUCCUAGGGAAUGAUGUGUUACAGAAAGACUUACAUGAAAAUGAAGGAUUUGAAUAUGCUGAUGUCCUUUAUCUUCUUCACUCAACAGAAAAGGAUAUUUGCUUAAGAGCAGGCUAUGCAUUAACACUUUUUGCCUUCAAUAAUCGCUUUCAACAAUACUUAAUAUUGGAAAGUGGAAUAAUGACCAUAUCUAUUUUUGAACGUUUUCUUGAAUCAACAGUUGAAACUGAGAAGGCAAUGGCAGCAUUUCAGAUUGUUGUACUGGCUAAAGUCAUUAGAGAUAUGGACCAUAUUACUUUGUCUGCAAGAGGUGUUACUAUUUUAGUUGAUAGUCUGUAUUCAGUUCAGACUUCUACUAUUGUCUUGACAGGGAAUUUAAUAGCAAGCCUGGCUCAUUCUAGAGCUGGUAUCCCAGAAGCAUUUACCACAUUAGGAACAAUCCAACGGCUCUGCUAUCAUUUGUACUCGGGAAUAGAAGAGGUUCGUGCAGCUUGUUCCUCUGCUCUUGGCUACUUAACAUACAAUGCAAAUGCUUUCCGCAUCCUAUUAAAAGAAUGCAGGAAUAAACCUAAUCAGUUCAUUCGUAUAAAAAAUAAUAUCAGCAGAGAUGCAAGUAUUAACCCAGCAUUUUUAAAGGAAUUUCAAAUGCAACAAACACUGGUGGGACUUCCUUCCUUAAGUCUGGAGAAGAAUGGAGGACCAUCCAUAAUUCCUAUCUUUAAAAGAGGAGAAAGCCCGAACCUGGCGCCCGGAAGUGAUGUCAUCGGAACUGUGCAAGGUCCCGUCCAGAGCUGGCUGCUGUUCCGCUAGCGAGCGGCAUGCUUAGUGAAGAAAAGCUUAAAGGCCGUCUUUGCCCAAAACGCUCUCUGUGCGCACCUGCAUUUCCCCCAGAUUUGCAGGUGAUGAGAGUUCUGUAAAAUUACACAGCUAGUGACUGAUCCAGCGGAGGCCGAAUACAGGUUUGUCUGACUACACAACAUCAAGUUCCAAACACUAAGCUACAUUAAAAAGAAAUUUUUUUUUUGC